UACUCCAGCACUCCAGCCUGGGCAACAGAGCGAGACUCCGUCUCAAAAAAAAUAAAAAAAUAAAAAAACCCCAACAAAACCAAACUGAGAGCUUCUCAAUUUGUAGUCAGAAAGAUUAAAAAACAAUUAGGCUGGGUGUGGUGCUCAUGCCUGUAAUCUUAGCACUUUGGGAAGCCUAGCUAGGAAGAUUGUUCAAGGCCAGGAGUUCAAGGCCAGCCCUAGCAACAUAGUGAGACCCCCCCUCAUCUCCAUACAAAAAAAAAAAAAAAAAUUUUUUUAAAUAGCUGAGUGUGGUGGUGCAUGCCUAUAGUCCUAGCUACUUGGGAGGCUGAGGCAGGAGGAAUGCUUCAGCCCAGGAGGUUGAAGCUGCAGUAAGCUAUGAUUGUACCAGUGUACUCCAACCUGGCCAACAGUGAGACCCUGUCUCAAAAAAUAAUAAUUAAAAGGGGACCAACCUCCUGAUACAGUGAUAUUUACUCUAGUGCACACCACCUAAAAACCUCAGGUACCAAUACUUGUACAUGUCUCAUUUUUGGACAAACACUGACUUGACCGAGCACUUCCUUCACUAGAAACAGAAGUGGACCCAGAGGGGGACUCCCUUGCCUGGGUCACACAGAGAAGGAGUAGCUGACCUGGGGUUAGAACUUGAGUCCUAGGCCAGUAUACUUUUCACAGUUAUGGCAGUUGUGGCUAUCUACAGACCUGUCCUCUGGGUCUAGUUUGGAAAAGCCUGACCAGGGAUGUGGAGGCCAGGUGUCCAAAGUGGAACAAGCUCCAAGCUGGUCCUAAAGGAGCCCCAAGAGAUUGGCUGGGGUUUCAGCUUAUGUCUGGUUUUCCAGAGGGGGCUGUCAGAAGAACUAAUGCUCUAUGGGAAGGGAGUACAAAAAAAGGGGCAGCAGCCCCGGGCACUGAAGCUCAUCUCUGUCUUUCUCUCUUCUUGCUGCCUUGGGCCUGGGUCAUUUCAGACAAACCUCAGCUCUACACCCUCGCCGUGAUCGGCCCAGGACCGCCAGAUUGCCAGCCAGCCCAGAUCUCUCGCCGUUACUCGGACUUUGAGCGGCUGCACCGAAACCUGCAGCGGCAAUUCCGGGGCCCAAUGGCUGCCAUCUCCUUCCCCCGUAAGCGGCUGCGCCGGAAUUUUACUGCAGAGACCAUUGCCCGCCGUAGCCGGGCCUUUGAGCAGUUUUUGGGUCACCUGCAGGCAGUGCCUGAGCUGCGCCAUGCCCCGGACCUGCAGGACUUCUUCGUGCUGCCGGAGCUGCGGCGGGCACAGAGCCUCACCUGUACUGGCCUCUAUCGUGAGGCUCUGGCACUCUGGGCCAAUGCCUGGCAGCUGCAAGCCCAGCUGGGCACCCCCUCUGGCCCAGACCGCCCCCUGCUGACCCUGGCUGGGCUGGCCGUGUGCCACCAGGAGCUGGAAGACCCUGGAGAGGCCCGGGCAUGCUGUGAGAAGGCCCUGCAGCUGCUUGGGGACAAGAGCCUCCACCCUUUGCUGGCACCCUUUCUGGAGGCCCAUGUCCGGCUCUCCUGGCGCCUGGGCCUGGACAAACGUCAAUCAGAGGCUCGGCUCCAAGCCCUGCAGGAGGCAGGCCUUACCCCCACACCACCCCCCAGUCUCAAAGAAUUGCUCAUCAAGGAGGUGCUGGACUAACCCUUGCCUAGAUUUAAGGCCACUGUGAGGAGAGGGGUUGCCCCAGAAGGCAGGGGAAGGACCUGAUGAGAACAGAAUAGCUGGGAGGCUGCAGAGGGUGCUGGGAGCCCCUAGAAGUUCCAAAAGAGAAUGUGAAGCAGAUCAAGGAAACUUCUGUUGAGCUAGGCUCAGGGUGAGCUUUGGCUGGGGUUGCCCUUGUGUAGUACAGGGAAGUCUGACACAGCCUCUCCAGCCUAUAAACAGCCGGGGGGCUGUGGCACAGGUUGGGGCAAUGUUCCCUUGUUGGUGGGCCCCCAAGCUGGCAAGGCCUCUUGGCUGAAGGCCAGGGACUCUGCCCCUGGAGUCCUGGAGUUAAGGGAUGAAGGCAAGGCUGCAGGUCUGGCCCAGGGGAAUUAAAAGCCAGCCACUCCAGUGGUAUCAGUCUCUUUAUUGGAUGUGAGGGCCAAAAGGGACUGUAACUCCUGUCUCAGGAAUGGGGAUAGAUGGGAGGUUCUUGAAGCCCCAGGCGAAGCUGGUACCUCUGGCUACAGCUUGCUCUCUGAGACCUGGGGCUUCACUCGGAUCACGCCCUCCUGGGCACAGGUCACAGCUAGGACUCCAUCCUGACGCCACAGCCGCCCAUGGACCAGCCCCCGAGAGCCACCUGUGGGUGAGGUGAAGGGUGAUGAUGGCCUGCUUCAGAACAGCCAAAUACACUUUUUUUUUUUUUCCUGAAACAGAGUCUCACUAAGUUGCCAGGCUGGUCUCAAGCGCCUGGGUUCAAGGGAUCCUCCCGCCUCAGCCUCCUGAGCAGCUGGGAUUACAGGCGCACAUCACCAUGCCCAACCUCCAAGUGGACUUCUUGCAAAGGGUCUGGCCCAGGGCAGGGCUGCCCCACACAAGGGUGCACUGAGUGUCGUGGCUGCUCCAAAUGCCCCUUCAUGAGCUUAUUAUGGACCGUCAUUGAGGGGUAACUCCUCCCACAGGAACCCCAGUUGACAGUUUAAAAGCACUUUCACACCUCUCCUCGCUUCCUCAAAAAGAUCACAGAGGGAGGAGCUCUGAGAACAGUCUCCUUCAACAGCUCGGCCAAGCAGAACUGCUGUACCUCUGACCACUUGUGUUAGGAAAACUAUCGGCUCCCUGUAUAAUAAAUCAAGCCAGGUCCUCCAAGUGGUAAUUCAUGAAAAAUAUCCCCACUACCACCACCAAGGGGAAGAAAGGACUCAGAAGAGAGGACUUGAGGCCAUGAGGUCUGGCCUCUUCCCUCCCCAUCUGGAGACUCUUUCUCCCUUGCUGGCUUUGGGCCCAAGUUUGAUGUUUAUGAGGAUGAUUGCUGGUUUCCCUUACACAUAGCAGAGCUCACUCAGUUCUCACAGUAGCCAAAUGAAGCAGUUAUGUGUUGUCCAGUUUUCCAGACCAGGACUGAAAUCCAGAGAGGGUCAGGAAUUUGGCCCCAUGAUGAAGCCAAAUCUGAACCCAUGUCCUCACUUCAAGGUUAUCAAUCUUGGAUUGUGAUGCUAUUGGUACUUGAGAAUACCCCUUAUCUGAGUAUAAAGAAUCCUUGAGUUUUGUCCUUGGUUUAUCAAGCAAAGCUUUUCUUCAUUUGAAAUGUACUCCCUUGGAAAGGAGGUCAGGGUUCUGAAGCUAGACAUUGAUGAACGAGUCUUGUUUCUCUCCCCUGCAAGGAAGGUCCAAGCAGGCCCUUAGGGACCACUGAAUGCCCCGAUCCCAAUCAGGUUAAUCAGAAUCACUUAGAGAACUUAAAAAUACAGUUUCCUGGACCUUAUCCAAGACCUACUGAGUGAGAAUCUUGAGGGUGGAAUCAGAAUCUAUUUUGAAAAGGCAUCCCCAAAUGGCAGUCUGAUGGACUGCGGGUUUGGAUACCACUGCUGUAAUGUAACCCUCUUUGUUUAGAUGAGGAAACUGAGGUUCAGAUGGAAGAUAUGAUUUGCCUAUUGUAAUACAAAGAAUCUGAACUGGU